GCACACUAGGCCCGCAGCUCCCUUCAGCGCCGCAGACCCCCUGACACCGCACCCGGUCCUCAGGCAGCGCGCCCCAGACCCCGGGUUCGGCACGCCGUCGUCGGCUUCCGGACAUCGCAACUUGCGCCCCUCUCGGGGAUCCUCCUCCCGGGCUCUGGACCCCAGGUGAUCCUAGGUCCCCAGCCGCCGGCGAACACCAUGGCCCCCCAGGGGGGUGAGGUAGGAGCAGCCUGAGUACCCCCAGAAGGUGCCCCGUCCACGCCCCUCCGGGCUGCGCGGCGGGAGUCUUCGGGGAGCUAUGCUGAGACCGGGUGGUGCGGAGGAAGCUGCGCAGCUCCCGCUUCGGCGCGCCAGCGCCCCGGUCCCUGUGCCGUCGCCCGCGGCCCCCGACGGCUCCCGGGCUUCGGCCCGCCUAGGUCUUGCCUGCCUUCUGCUCCUGCUGCUGCUGACGCUGCCGGCCCGCGUAGACACGUCCUGGUGGUACAUUGGGGCACUGGGGGCACGAGUGAUCUGUGACAAUAUCCCUGGUUUGGUGAGCCGGCAGCGGCAGCUGUGCCAGCGUUACCCAGACAUCAUGCGUUCAGUGGGCGAGGGUGCCCGAGAAUGGAUCCGAGAGUGUCAGCACCAAUUCCGCCACCACCGCUGGAACUGUACCACCCUGGACCGGGACCACACCGUCUUUGGCCGUGUCAUGCUCAGAAGUAGCCGAGAGGCAGCUUUUGUAUAUGCCAUCUCAUCAGCAGGGGUAGUCCACGCUAUUACUCGCGCCUGUAGCCAGGGUGAACUGAGUGUGUGCAGCUGUGACCCCUACACCCGUGGCCGACACCAUGACCAGCGUGGGGACUUUGACUGGGGUGGCUGCAGUGACAACAUCCACUACGGUGUCCGUUUUGCCAAGGCCUUCGUGGAUGCCAAGGAGAAGAGGCUUAAGGAUGCCCGGGCCCUCAUGAACUUACAUAAUAACCGCUGUGGUCGCACGGCUGUGCGGCGGUUUCUGAAGCUGGAGUGUAAGUGCCAUGGCGUGAGUGGUUCCUGUACUCUGCGCACCUGCUGGCGUGCACUCUCAGAUUUCCGCCGCACAGGUGAUUACCUGCGGCGACGCUAUGAUGGGGCUGUGCAGGUGAUGGCCACCCAAGAUGGUGCCAACUUCACCGCAGCCCGCCAAGGCUAUCGCCGUGCCACCCGGACUGAUCUUGUCUACUUUGACAACUCUCCAGAUUACUGUGUCUUGGACAAGGCUGCAGGUUCCCUAGGCACUGCAGGCCGUGUCUGCAGCAAGACAUCAAAAGGAACAGACGGUUGUGAAAUCAUGUGCUGUGGCCGAGGGUACGACACAACUCGAGUCACCCGUGUUACCCAGUGUGAGUGCAAAUUCCACUGGUGCUGUGCUGUACGGUGCAAGGAAUGCAGAAAUACUGUGGACGUCCAUACUUGCAAAGCCCCCAAGAAGGCAGAGUGGCUGGACCAAACCUGAACACACAGAUACCUCACUCAUCCCUCCAAUUCAAGCCUCUCAACUCAAAAGCACAAGAUCCUUGCAUGCACACCUUCCUCCACCCUCCACCCUGGGCUGCUACCGCUUCUAUUUAAGGAUGUAGAGAGUAAUCCAUAGGGACCAUGGUGUCCUGGCUGGUUCCUUAGCCCUGGGAAGGAGUUGUCAGGGGAUAUAAGAAACUGAGCAAGCUCCCUGAUUUCCCGCUCUGGAGAUUUGAAGGGAGAGUAGAAGAGAUAGGGGGUCUUUAGAGUGAAAUGAGUUGCACUAAAGUACGUAGUUGAGGCUCCUUUUUUCUUUCCUUUGCACCAGCUUCCCGAUACUUCUUGGUGUGCAAGAGGAAGGGUACCUGUAGAGAGCUUCUUUUUGUUUCUACCUGGCCAAAGUUAGAUGGGACAAAGAUGAAUGGCAUGUCCCUUCUCUGAAGUCCGUUUGAGCAGAACUACCUGGUACCCCGAAAGAAAAUCUUAGGCUACCACAUUCUAUUAUUGAGAGCCUGAGAUGUUAGCCAUAGUGGACAAGGUUCCAUUCACAUGCUCAUAUGUUUAUAAACUGUGUUUUGUAGAAGAAAAAGAAUCAUAACAAUACAAACACACAUUCAUUCUCUCUUUUUCUCUCUACCAUUCUCAACCUGUAUUGGACAGCACUGCCUCUUUUGCUUACUUGCUGCCUGUUCAAACUGAGGUGGAAUGCAGUGGUUCCCAUGCUUAACAAAUCAUUAAAACACCCUAGAACACUCCUAGGAUAGAUUAAUGUAGUAAGUCUGGCUAGGCCUUGUGUUGCCUUUUUUUUUUUUUUUUUUUUCUUUUCUUUUCUUCUCUUCCCAUGCACUAUUCUGGAGGUUUGCCAGGUUUGGGGAGACAUGGAGUAAAAGAAAGAUAGGCAACUCAUGGAUGGUGGGAGAGCAGGUAAGCAGGUCUGAUCUCAAGGGCCCACAUGAGGCAUCAGUAUAUAUUAGGCAGGUAGGGAUCUCUGGCUUUGGUAAUUCUUUAUGAGAGGAUCCUAGCCUUUGAAGCUGGGAGCAGGAGUCAGUGGCUACAGUGGGAAGGAGUACUGCAGGUUGGGGCCAAAGUGAUACACAGCUUAGAAGGCAGCCUUCCUCCACUUACUCAACAAAUCUUUAUUUAGUGACUCUCCAAGUCCUAGUGAUUAUUAUUAUUGUUCACUCCACAUUUGGCUUAAUGGGUAAUGCUAUUACCCAUUGCCUAACUAGGUUUGCAGUAGUGGAAUCUCCAGAGAUAGCAGGCUUAGUAAGCUGGAGGUAGGACAUGAAGUCCCCCAAAACUUGAUGUCCUAUUUUUAUGUGAGUUGGACAGUGGUUAUCUUUUGCCUGUUGAUAUCUUAAAGCAGCAGAGUGGUAUAGAAAUUUGCGGUUAUGACAGACCCGGGUUAAAAAUCACAGCUGUGCCAUUUGCUUUGAUAUUUUGAGCAAGGUAGCUAAAUUUUCUGAGCUUCUAUUUUCUCAUCUGUAAAAUGAGGAUACGUACCUGUUCUUUUUUUUCUUUCUUUUUAUUUCUUUUAGAGAUAGGGUCUCGCUUUGUUGCCCAGGCUGGAGUGCACUGGCAUGAUCAUGGCUCACUGCAGCCUCAAAUUCCCAGGCUCAAGCAAUCCUCCCACCUCAGCCUCCCCAUUAGCUGGGACUACAGGGCCAUGCCAUCAUGCCCAGCUAAUUUAAACAUAGUUUUCAGAGAUGGAGCUCACUAUGUUGCCCAGGCUGGUCUUGAAUUCUUGGUCUCAAGCAAUCCUCCCACUGCAGCCUUCCAAAGUGCUGGGCGUACAAGCGCAAGCCACUGUGCCCAGCUGUCAGACGCUGAGUUUUAAUUAUGCACCAAACUCCAGCCCGCAGAUCCUCUUCACCAAAGCCCCUGGCUGGUCUAGCCCAUCAUGACUUCUCUAGGAACAGUCCUUCUUUAGGACUAUAAAGUAUUAACAAAAGUCUGUAGAUUAAGGAGCCUGCAUAAAGAAUUCUGGAUACAGGCCCCUGUCUUUCCAAAGUUCCUCUCCAAUAUCCCUUGGGGUCCUCAUGUUUUUGAAGCAGCUUCACUCUGCACAGGCAGCAGGAGGUUGGGGGAGCCAUAGCUCUGGGCCACGGGGGCAGAUUUAUUUGGAUGAUAGGACUAAUAUUUGUGUAACCUGCUGAGACCUGUGUGGGAGAGUUUAGGGUGGUUUUUCUUUUGGUGAGGGGAUUUGCUCUGGUUUCACAUCCAUUAACACAAAACAUGAGCUAGUCAGGGCCCUUGUGGUCUGCGGUAAGGGGAUGCCUGUGGAGAAAUGGGCCUGAGUGAGUCAGGCCAAGAGAAUGUCUUCCUUCAGAAUGGAGUCAACUGGAUAACUGAUGAGCCAAUGGUGGGAUUAAGGAGGGGGAAAUGGGAGGGGAAGAGAACAGCUGACAUCUUGAGGAAAGCUUUGGGGUAGUGGAGAGGUAAGGGGGUCAUGGUCAGUCUGAACUCAACAAUAGGGCUGAAUGAAUUUACCAAAGGAAGCUGCCUUAUAUUAUAUGCCAGGCUGCUGGGGAAAGCCUCAGGUCCUGGCCAGCCCCUGUUCUCACAAGAACAUGCAGGUUACCACAUAAAUAAUGGCAUAUGCCUUCCAUAGGACGUCAACCUGACUUAAAUCUACCUAUACCCUACUCUCUAUUCUUUGGUUUUUGGUUCUCAUCCCUGUGGAAGGAAAUGGGCCUCUUCUGGCAUCUCAUGCUACUCUGUGCUUUUCCUUGGGCUCCAAAUUCUAGCUCAUAAAGAUGCAAGUUUUGCAAUUUCCUAUAAAUGGUUAAGAAAAGAGCAAGCUGUCCAGAGAGUGAGAAGUUUGAAAAGAGAGGUGCAUAAGAGAGAAAUGAUGUCCAUUUGAGCCCCACCACGGAGGUUAUGUGGUCCCAAAAGGAAUGAUGGCCAAGCAAUUAAUUUUUCCUCCUAGUUCUUAGCUUGCUUCUGCAUUGAUUGGCUUUACACAACUGGCAUUUAGUCUGCAUUACACAAAUAGACACUAAUUUAUUUGGAACAAGCAGCAAAAUGAGAACUUUAUUUGGUGCAGUCAGGGCUCCAUUUAGUUCCCUCACUCUGCUUCUAAUCACCCCUUCUCCCAGCCCUCUUCUAUUUGAUAGAGGUCUGUCCCUCAGAUCAGCAAUGUCUUAGCCCCUCUCCUCUCUUCCAUUCCUUCCUGUUGGUACUCAUUUCUUCUAACUUUUAAUAAACAUUUAGGUAUAAUACAUUACAGUAAGUGCUAUUUAGAUACAAACUUAAAACAUACUAUAUAUUUUAAGGAUCUAAGAAUCCUUUAGAGAAGGCACAUGACUGAAGUACCUCAGCUGCGCAGCCUGUAGCCAGUUUUUUUAAUGUAAAAGUAAGAAUGCCAGCCUUAACCUAGCCCUGCAGAUAAAAGCUAACUUUUAUUAAUACCAGCCCUGAAUAAUGGCACUAAUCCACACUCUUCCUUAGAGUGAUGCUGGAAAAAUAAAAUCAGGGGCUUCAGAUUAAAAAAAAAAACAAAAAACAAAAAACAAAAACAAACAUUGCCUGGCCCUGAGGGUCUGUUUGCAAAACUUCUUGUAGAUCUAAUUUCUGAACACUCACUGCUUCAUUUCUAUUCCUCCUGUUGCAGGGAGUAAUUUCUUCUCCUUUGUCUCACUUCCCUUAUCAAGAACACCAACCAGUAAGUCUUUGCCAAAUUCUCAGACCCACUCAGGACACGAGUCUCUACAUGGCUUAACAGAAGAGAGAUAAUUAGGAUUUUUUUUUCCUCAGUCUUUCUGAGGUUUUUAUUUAAAUGCACUCAGUGGUCAUAGGGCAGAAGCUCAAGCUAGCUGGGGCGAAGGGAGGACGCCAGGGAGAGUAUGUUUCUCAUCCCUGGGAGGCAUUCAGCCUAGCUCCUGCAGCCAAAUUACAGCACCAGAGAACAAUGUGAUGCAUUCCUGGGCAGGUCGGUGGGACCCUGGGCGCCUGGGCCUUGUGGAGAGAGGUGCCAGACACAGAGUUCUCCGUAAGCAAUCCUGCAGAGCCGCCCCCUGGGUGCAGAAAUGAAAUACGGGAGAGCUUCACAUUACACAGAGACCUGUAGCUCACACCUGGUUAUUGAUGGCCUUGGUGGAGGCCUCUGCCCCGACCCUCCACUUGGGAACUGCCUGCUACUACGGGGGUUGGGCAUCUUUGAAGCAAUGUUGGAUAACAAGAAAGAGAUGCUUCCUUUUCACUCUUUGCCCUCCCUGUCAGCCUGAGCACAACCAUGAGGUUACACACACACACACAGAGGUGUACAUAUACAGACACAUAGAGAACUUCUCUCAGGCUGCAUAGGAGUUCUGCUCAUCCUCCUCUCCCCAACAAUUAAAAAAAAAAGCAAUUAGAUUUCGAUCCAGUACUUCAAAAAGGAUACCAAUAGGGUCUGGCUUUAAUCAAGGAAUAUCUACAAAGUCACAUUACCAACCUGCAGGCAACUCUUUGGUUUGGGGACCAGAACUCCUCUGGUGGGUGGUUGGGGGAAGGAUGCAGGAAGGGCAUGGUGAGGAGAGAUCAGUGGUGAAGAAUUACCAUCAAAGCAGAGUGGCUGAGACUGUAUAAGUUCGCAAGGCUGGUUCAUGCCAGAGAUAGUGAGAUGUGCACCCUAUGUGCUGAGAAUGAUGGAGCAGUCUCCUAUGACUGCAUGGGGUAUAACUGCCAAGCCUACUGCUCAUGACCUGUGGUUGUUUUUAACUCUUAACUGGGUUAGAAAACUGGAGAGCUUUGGAUUCCAGGGAUGAUCUCCAUAAGAGAGAAGCACUGGAAAAGACCAAGUGGUGGCUUUAUUAGGGUAAAUAUAUCACAGUUGCUACAGUGAAUUGAGCUUUCUCAGAAGCUAUUAUUUUCUUUGGGUGAUUGGCAGGUAUAGGGCAAUAGCCAGUGGGGUGUCAGUAAUAUGCCCUGUCCCUGACCUCAAAGGUAAAGGGAUAGAAAAGAGAGGGCGUUGACAAACUCAUUUUCCCACUUCCCACUCAUGGCUUAUAUUAUCUCUGAGCAUCUCGGUGGCUAUUCCUCAUUUACUUAAGAUGUUUUAGUCAUUCUGGAUGUGCAAAUGCAAGGCAAGCAUUCUCCCACUGGCCCCCUAACGGUUAACUAUCCUGGCUUAAAAUUUUCCUUUGCUCACUUCCAUUCUAUGAGUAUAUCGAUGGAGCAGCUGGACAUUAGAGUUCUUUCUCUUUGACCAAAGGAGCCAAAAUGCGGUGACUUGACUUCAACCCCAACAGCCCCUGUAAGUAGCCCUGGCCAAACAGAAAGGCUAAGCUGAAUGAAGAAAAAAGGAAGACAAUUUCAUCUACAGUUGUCCUUUUUGACAGCUUCCAAGGGGGGUUUGCCUAGGAAUAACAAUAUUCAUAAGAAGCUUUUUCAUAUGCAAAAUGCUUUAGCAUAUAUGUAAUCCUCACAACAACCCUGUGAGGUAGGGGUUACUGUCACUUUACAGAUGCUGUUCAGAAAAAUUUGGUGAUUUGUCCAAGGUCACAUGAACAGUGCGUGGCUCAGCCAGAACUCAAACCUAGGUCUUCUGACUUCAAAUCCUGUGUAUUCUCCUCAAAGCCUGAGGAUGCCCAGGGUUGGGGGCACCAGAGUCCCAGCACCUUCAAAACAGAAAUUGAUACAAAAUGUUCAAGCCCUGUAGGAGUCCCAGGACAGCCAAGAGAGUAUAUCUGAGCACAGUUUACAAAGGAACAGCCUAGGCCCUCCUGAACCUUAUCAACCAAUGGCUCUUUUGCCAUUUCUGCCACUAUUACCACCAGUACCAUGUGACCACUAUACAACAUAUUCCACAUUUAAACAACUCUGGCUCCUAAUUCUACUCCUUUUUUCCCCUUCAGAUUAACAUUAAAAAUUUUAUCUAGUCCUUUUGAAAUUAUGCUAAAUGUAUAGACACAGUAGAAGUAGUCAUGACAGAAAAUUAUUAAGGCUUUGAAAAUAUGUAUCAGAGGCCGGGUGCAGUGGCUCAUGCCUGUAAUCCCAGCACUUUGGGAGGCCGAGGUGGGGCAGAUCACGAGGUCAGGAGAUUGAGACCAUCCUGGCUAACACGGUGAAACCCUGUCUCUACUAAAAAUACAAAAAAAUUAGCCGGGCCUGGUGGCGGGCGCCUGUAGUCCCAGCUACUGGGGAGGCUGAGGCAGGAGAAUGGCGUGAACCCAGGAGGCAGAGCUUGCAGUGAGCCAAGAUGCACCACUGCACUCCAGCCUGGGAGACAGAGCGAGACUCCGUCACAAAAAAAAAAAAAAAGAAGGUAUGUAUUAGAAUUUUCUUUGAGAUUUCACUCCUUUUAAAAAUGACGUCAACUCCUGGGUUAGGAAAGCAAGAUGAGGGAAUAAGUGUCCUAAGAAACUCCCAUCCCAAGCCAGACAGAUGCCUACCCGUGGCCUGGCAAAGGUCCUGGGAUCUCAAGCUGAUGCAAGCAAUUUGUGUACACCAAGGCAAGGGGUCUCAAUCCUGCAGAGAAACCCAUGAGAUGAGGCAGACAGCAGAUUUUCACUUGAUCAAACACUUGCUGCUCUCAACCCCUCUUUGUUUUCCCAUCCAAAAUCUGGACCUCUGUUUAGGCGCAAGACAGUGAGUAAGAGCAGCUCCAAAAGAUGACGUAUGCAAGGGGAACUCUUCUGUUCAAUCCUGUAAUGUUUUCUGUUAGAGACAGCAUAGGCUACCUAUCCUAAUCCUGCACCCCAACUGUUAAGACAGAAGGGAAAAGUACAAUGUUCAUCAAUCAUAGCUCUGGGAUGCUGCAGCUCCCUGACCUGGGCCCCUACUUGAGCUAGGAGAAGAACACCUCAUGAAAACAGUCUACCUAUAGUCAGGACUUCCCCAAGGCAGACUUUAUUUUUUGGUCCAUCGAUCUUGGCUCUCACUGUUCUCCCUGCUUCCCACCCCCAACUGCCUCUGCAUGUGGGCUCAGAAGUCAUCAUCUAAAGAAUUCCAUUGCUCACCUCCUGCAUAGCAGCACAGCCCCAUGAGGCCACACACCAGAUGGAGGGGAUAAAAGUACGAGGUCAUGGCUUCUUGCAAGAGGCUUUUUCUUAAACUAACCCUGACUCCUGGAAAAGAGGCAGAGCAGGAGAGUGUUGAAUGAGCUGCUGAUGACAGCAGCUUCAUAGGUCUUGUGUAUAAAGGAAGGAAAAAGCUAACUUGGCUUUCCGUGGAAAUUUACCUACUCCCAUUUUCAGGUCUACUCCUGGUCUCACAUCUACUUCUUGAAGGUGUCUAAGUAGAAUGCAGAGAUUGUCAAGCUAGAGGGUUAACUCCUUCCCAAUUGUAGGGAUCUAUUCAGCAGGCUGCCACACACAUGCUGAGGUGGAGGCCAACCCUGAACACAUGCGCUGCUUCUUUAGGAAUGUAACUAUGAAGUAAAAGGAAACAGUAAGGAAGGUGAACUGGAACUCUGGGGAAACUGAAAAGGUCAUCAAUAGGCCUUCAAAAUAUUUGUGUGUAAUAAGUAGACACAAGAGGCUGGAGGAAGAUGAUCAUUCCUAGAAUAAUUAUGCUUACUGGGUGACAAUAUACAGAAGCAACAAUUACAAUAAAAUGAAACAGUUUAAUGGACUAGGAAGCAGAAGUCUGAGAAUAAAGGAAUUAGGUUAAUGAGAUUAAGCAGAGAUGGCAUUCCACAGGAGGUGACUUUUGAGUUGAAUUUUUAAAAGAUAGCUUUAUGUGUUUUAUGAACUGACUGAGGGCAGUCAGAAGAAGGCAUUCUAAAUAGAGGGAACUGGUAUGUGCUGAAACUUAGAAGCAGGAAUGUACAAGCAAUAUAUAAGGAAUUUCAAGCAAGUACACAUUAUAUACACUGGGGAAUACAGAGAAAUUAGAAUGCUGAGAUCAGGGCUUAAAUAAUGUGAGGUGACUGUGUGCACCUAGACUGUCAAAUGGUUCAGCAUCCCCUAUAGAGCCACAUAGUAUCUUGAUUUAUGUCAGUAAACAUCAGGGCACCUAUGGAAAAGCACAAGGAUGAGUCCAUUUGUUACAGACCCAGGGACUAACAGAGAUCUACACUGUAAAGUUCAACAAAAUGCUACAUAUCAUUAACUACAGCUCCUUAUCAUUUGAGAUUCUGGGCUAAGUAAGAGAUAUCAAAUAUCCUAUCCAGUACUGUGAUACAUUAAUGUAGGCUUACAGGCCCAGAACCUGGCAUAAAUCAAGCCAAACCCUUAAGAAAUUAGAAUGUGAAAAGAAAAUAAUUUAAAAUAGAAAAUACAUGCUGCUUUUCCUCACUCCCAAACUUAAAACUUGACUGGUCCUACAUAUUCUACUUGGUAUAUUGAAUUUUUGCAGCUAGCAGAUUUAUCGUAUCUGAGGCCAUAGUGAAUAGAAGAGCUGCAAAAGAGCUUUAGAGACUGCAAAACCAGCUCACUAAUAAAUGAGGAACUUUAUUCUAAUUUACUACCAGGGGCUGAAGUAGCAGCCAAAGAAGGAGACAAAUUCUAACUUCAUGAUCUCUAGUUAGGUGUCUAUUUUCCUGCAUUUGCUAAAGGUAAAAAUCGCUACUUAUGGGGCUUUUGUCAUACUUCUUAACCAAACUUCCCUAACUUCUGAGGAUAAAAACCAUAAGGGCAAUCUUAUUCUUCCAAAGCAGUUCCCUGGUGCCACUUUCAGAAACAGAGUAUUGAACUAUGGGUCUGACCCAGUGUGGCACUGAGUGUGUGUGUGUUUGUGUGUUUGUGUGUGUGUGUACACUGAAUAAGCCAAAACGUGUGCCAUAUUCUAGGUUUCUGCUUUACUUAACUGGCAAAAUUUGGUGCUGUAAGGGAGGCAGCCACAAAACCAGUGAUAGCAUUUGUUAGUAUCAUCUUAGUUCUCUUCCCUCCCCUAGGUAGUUUAUAAAGGGUGAUUUCUGAAACCCUUCACAAAAGAAAAGCUCAAGGGUUUACAUUCAACUGUGACAGCACUAUGAAUUCAUUAAGAAGCAUGUUUCAGGUUGCACUGUAAUUUCCCUAUGUAAUACAAACCCAUGGAAUCUGACAUAAGCUGAUUGCUCAUGCUGGUUGUUUUAUUUACAUUUCUGAAUGGAAAGGAUUUCAAUACUCAUAAAAUAUCUAACUGGCUUAUUUUUCAUCUGUUCUCCCAGAGAAGCUAUUAUAAGAUAGGCAUAGAGACAGAAGUCUCAACUUGUAUAACUGGUUAAGCAACCAGGGAAAUGUUAUUGCUCAAAAUGCAAUUUUAAAAAAUUCAAUAUGGAACUUGAGGCCAAAAAAACAGAAGGUUACUCUCAAUGCCAUCCAAAAGAUAAAAGUUAAAAAAAAAAAAAAAAAAAAAGGUAACUAUGCUCAUUAUUUUCAACCAAGUUCUAUGGAGGUGGUACCUUCACAGGAGCUCAGUGGAACUGGGGUUUACUUACAUCUUUUUUCUGGGAACCUAAUGUUAGCAGACACAGUUGCUAGUUUGAACAGGAAUGCAGAUGAAUGGAUGAAAGUGGGCUCCCUACCACCCAGAAAUAUGAAUGUGCCUCCUUACCAAUAUGCUACAAAUCAGACCUCUGAAUUAGAAGAUGCCAUCAUGCAACUAACUUACUAUCUGGAGAUGUGUAUUUUGUUAACCUAGGCAAAGAAUAACAAUUUCUGCUUAUUCCAGUAGGUGUGACAAGCUCAGAGAAGUGAGCGACAAGCUAGAGAAGUAAUAAUUACCAAUAAAGUAAAUUCCAAAGCCGAA